GCCAGUUUUGGGCUGGUUGGCGCGGAAUCGGGAGAUUCGGGACCAUGGCACCUGUGCACGGCGACGACUGUGAGAUAGGGGCGAGUGCUCUGUCAGAUUCAGGGAGUUUUGUAUCUUCUCGAGCCCGGCGAGAAAAAAAAUCAAAGAAGGGGCGCCAAGAAGCCCUAGAAAGACUGAAAAAGGCUAAAGCUGGUGAGAAGUAUAAAUAUGAAGUCGAGGACUUCACAGGUGUUUAUGAAGAAGUUGAUGAAGAACAGUAUUCGAAGCUGGUUCAGGCACGCCAGGAUGAUGACUGGAUUGUGGAUGAUGAUGGUAUUGGCUAUGUGGAAGAUGGCCGAGAGAUUUUUGAUGAUGACCUUGAAGAUGAUGCCCUUGAUGCUGAUGAGAAAGGAAAAGAUGGUAAAGCACGCAAUAAAGACAAGAGGAAUGUAAAGAAGCUCGCAGUGACAAAACCGAACAACAUUAAGUCAAUGUUCAUUGCUUGUGCUGGAAAGAAAACUGCAGAUAAAGCUGUAGACUUGUCCAAGGAUGGUCUGCUAGGUGACAUUCUACAGGAUCUUAACACUGAGACACCUCAAAUAACUCCACCACCUGUAAUGAUACUGAAGAAGAAAAGAUCCAUUGGAGCUUCACCGAAUCCUUUCUCUGUGCACACCGCCACGGCAGUUCCUUCAGGAAAAAUUGCUUCCCCUGUCUCCAGAAAGGAGCCUCCAUUAACUCCUGUUCCUCUUAAACGUGCUGAAUUUGCUGGCGAUGAUGUACAGGUCGAGAGUACAGAAGAAGAGCAGGAGUCAGGGGCAAUGGAGUUUGAAGAUGGUGACUUUGAUGAGCCCAUGGAAGUUGAAGAGGUGGACCUGGAGCCUAUGGCUGCCAAGGCUUGGGACAAAGAGAGUGAGCCAGCAGAGGAAGUGAAACAAGAGGCGGAUUCUGGGAAAGGGACCGUGUCCUACUUAGGAAGUUUUCUCCCGGAUGUCUCUUGUUGGGACAUUGAUCAAGAAGGUGAUAGCAGUUUCUCAGUGCAAGAAGUUCAAGUGGAUUCCAGUCACCUCCCAUUGGUAAAAGGGGCAGAUGAGGAACAAGUAUUCCACUUUUAUUGGUUGGAUGCUUAUGAGGAUCAGUACAACCAACCAGGUGUGGUAUUUCUGUUUGGGAAAGUUUGGAUUGAAUCAGCCGAGACCCAUGUGAGCUGUUGUGUCAUGGUGAAAAAUAUCGAGCGAACGCUUUACUUCCUUCCCCGUGAAAUGAAAAUUGAUCUAAAUACGGGGAAAGAAACAGGAACUCCAAUUUCAAUGAAGGAUGUUUAUGAGGAAUUUGAUGAGAAAAUAGCAACAAAAUAUAAAAUUAUGAAGUUCAAGUCUAAGCCAGUGGAAAAGAACUAUGCUUUUGAGAUACCUGAUGUUCCAGAAAAAUCUGAGUACUUGGAAGUUAAAUACUCGGCUGAAAUGCCACAGCUUCCUCAAGAUUUGAAAGGAGAAACUUUUUCUCAUGUAUUUGGGACCAACACAUCUAGCCUGGAACUGUUCUUGAUGAACAGAAAGAUCAAAGGACCUUGUUGGCUUGAAGUAAAAAGUCCACAGCUCUUGAAUCAGCCAGUCAGUUGGUGUAAAGUUGAGGCAAUGGCUUUGAAACCAGACCUGGUGAAUGUAAUUAAGGAUGUCAGUCCACCACCGCUUGUCGUGAUGGCUUUCAGCAUGAAGACAAUGCAGAAUGCAAAGAACCAUCAAAAUGAGAUUAUUGCUAUGGCAGCUUUGGUCCAUCACAGUUUUGCAUUGGAUAAAGCAGCCCCAAAGCCUCCCUUUCAGUCACACUUCUGUGUUGUGUCUAAACCAAAGGACUGUAUUUUUCCAUAUGCUUUCAAAGAAGUCAUUGAGAAAAAGAAUGUGAAGGUUGAGGUUGCUGCAACAGAAAGAACACUGCUAGGUUUUUUCCUUGCAAAAGUUCACAAAAUUGAUCCUGAUAUCAUUGUGGGUCAUAAUAUUUAUGGGUUUGAACUGGAAGUACUACUGCAGAGAAUUAAUGUGUGCAAAGCUCCUCACUGGUCCAAGAUAGGUCGACUGAAGCGAUCCAACAUGCCAAAGCUUGGGGGCCGGAGUGGAUUUGGUGAAAGAAAUGCUACCUGUGGUCGAAUGAUCUGUGAUGUGGAAAUUUCAGCAAAGGAAUUGAUUCGUUGUAAAAGCUACCAUCUGUCUGAACUUGUUCAGCAGAUUCUAAAAACUGAAAGGGUUGUAAUCCCAAUGGAAAAUAUACAAAAUAUGUACAGUGAAUCUUCUCAACUGUUAUACCUGUUGGAACACACCUGGAAAGAUGCCAAGUUCAUUUUGCAGAUCAUGUGUGAGCUAAAUGUUCUUCCAUUAGCAUUGCAGAUCACUAACAUCGCUGGGAACAUUAUGUCCAGGACGCUGAUGGGUGGACGAUCCGAGCGUAACGAGUUCUUGUUGCUUCAUGCAUUUUACGAAAACAACUAUAUUGUGCCUGACAAGCAGAUUUUCAGAAAGCCUCAGCAAAAACUGGGAGAUGAAGAUGAAGAAAUUGAUGGAGAUACCAAUAAAUACAAGAAAGGACGUAAGAAAGCAGCUUAUGCUGGAGGCUUGGUUUUGGACCCCAAAGUUGGUUUUUAUGAUAAGUUCAUUUUGCUUCUGGACUUCAACAGUCUAUAUCCUUCCAUCAUUCAGGAAUUUAACAUUUGUUUUACAACAGUACAAAGAGUUGCUUCAGAGGCACAGAAAGUUACAGAGGAUGGAGAACAAGAACAGAUCCCUGAGUUGCCAGAUCCAAGCUUAGAAAUGGGCAUUUUGCCCAGAGAGAUCCGGAAACUGGUAGAACGGAGAAAACAAGUCAAACAGCUAAUGAAACAGCAAGACUUAAAUCCAGACCUUAUUCUUCAGUAUGACAUUCGACAGAAGGCUUUGAAGCUCACAGCGAACAGUAUGUAUGGUUGCCUGGGAUUUUCCUAUAGCAGAUUUUACGCCAAACCACUGGCUGCCUUGGUGACAUACAAAGGAAGGGAGAUUUUGAUGCAUACGAAAGAGAUGGUACAAAAGAUGAAUCUUGAAGUUAUUUAUGGAGAUACAGAUUCAAUUAUGAUAAACACCAAUAGCACCAAUCUGGAAGAAGUAUUUAAGUUGGGAAACAAGGUAAAAAGUGAAGUGAAUAAGUUGUACAAACUGCUUGAAAUAGACAUUGAUGGGGUUUUCAAGUCUCUGCUACUGCUGAAAAAAAAGAAGUACGCUGCUCUGGUUGUUGAGCCAACGUCGGAUGGGAAUUAUGUCACCAAACAGGAGCUCAAAGGAUUAGAUAUAGUUAGAAGAGAUUGGUGUGAUCUUGCUAAAGACACUGGAAACUUUGUGAUUGGCCAGAUUCUUUCUGAUCAAAGCCGGGACACUAUAGUGGAAAACAUUCAGAAGAGGCUGAUAGAAAUUGGAGAAAAUGUGCUAAAUGGCAGUGUCCCAGUGAGCCAGUUUGAAAUUAACAAGGCAUUGACAAAGGAUCCCCAGGAUUACCCUGAUAAAAAAAGCCUACCUCAUGUACAUGUUGCCCUCUGGAUAAAUUCUCAAGGAGGCAGAAAGGUGAAAGCUGGAGAUACUGUGUCAUAUGUCAUCUGUCAGGAUGGAUCAAACCUCACUGCAAGUCAGAGGGCCUAUGCGCCUGAGCAGCUGCAGAAACAGGAUAAUCUAACCAUUGACACCCAGUACUACCUGGCCCAGCAGAUCCACCCAGUCGUGGCUCGGAUCUGUGAACCAAUAGACGGAAUUGAUGCUGUCCUCAUUGCAACGUGGUUGGGACUUGACCCCACCCAAUUUAGAGUUCAUCAUUAUCAUAAAGAUGAAGAGAAUGAUGCUCUACUUGGUGGCCCAGCACAGCUCACUGAUGAAGAGAAAUACAGGGACUGUGAAAGAUUCAAAUGUCCAUGCCCUACAUGUGGAACUGAGAAUAUUUAUGAUAAUGUCUUUGAUGGUUCGGGAACAGAUAUGGAGCCCAGCUUGUAUCGUUGCAGUAACAUCGAUUGUAAGGCUUCACCUCUGACCUUUACAGUACAACUGAGCAACAAAUUGAUCAUGGACAUUAGACGUUUCAUUAAAAAGUACUAUGAUGGCUGGUUGAUAUGUGAAGAGCCAACCUGUCGCAAUCGAACUCGUCACCUUCCCCUUCAAUUCUCCCGAACUGGGCCUCUUUGCCCAGCCUGCAUGAAAGCUACACUUCAACCAGAGUAUUCUGACAAGUCCCUGUACACCCAGCUGUGCUUUUACCGGUACAUUUUUGAUGCGGAGUGUGCACUGGAGAAACUUACUACCGAUCAUGAGAAAGGCCUGGUGGUAACAUCUGUAGGCCCUCUUGUUUCCUAACAUGCCACCCAGAAGAACUAGGCUGCCCCUUUUAAGGUACUUCAUAGUUUCCUAUUGUCCUUUCACGUGUGUAACACGAGUUCUCACAGUACUCCUGUGAGGCAGCAGUGGAUUGUGCUCAUUAUAUUGAUGAAGAAAUUAAAGUUACUAAAGUUCCUUGACAUUUGCAGAUUUAACGCUUGUCGCUUGAACUCUUUGCAAGUGAUACUGAAGGUAGGUAACAUGUUAGUGUGUGUUAUUUUGCUGAUGCCAGAUUUAAAUUGAACUGAAAGAAUAUCCAGUCACUUAACUAAUGAGCAAGCCAAGCCUACUGCUCCUCACCCACACUGCCACGGGGUCCUGUUCUGUGUUCCCCAUCAGCUAAGUAGUUACACUCAUGAAGUGCUAAUAGUUAUAUUACUUUGUGGAAAAUGGUCUCCAAAACAAAGACAACAGCUAGUACUGAAAAGGGUCUUAAAAGGUAGUAUUUUUUAAGCCAGAAAAUAAGAGUUUUAUAGAAGAAAUUAUAUGCUUUAGUGUAUAUGGGAAUGUGGAGAUUUUGGAAAGUCUCAAGAUGGGUCCCAUUUCAGUGUUAAGGAUUUCCGCUAUAUUUCCUGAACUGUUAAAGUGAAAGCAGGAAAGUUUCAUCAUGAAAGUAGCAAAGAGCCCCUGUGGUCCUCUCUAAGCUAGUUGACAUCCUUAGAAUUUACUUGGUUAAAUCCUUAACAAAAUAUUAAAAAGAAGACUGUGUCAGAGAGCACCUGUCUGGUCCUUUUCUUCUUAUUGCCACUUUUUGAAGCCCACUGGUUGUGUUCUGUUUUUUGGUUUUUUUUUGAGACGGAGUCUCACUCUGUCGCCCAGGCUAGAGUGCAGUGGUGUGAUCUUGGCUCACUACAAGCUCUGCCUCCUGGGUUCACGCCAUUCUCCUGCCUCAGCCUCCCGAGUAGCUGGGACUACAGGCAUCUGCCACCACGCCCGGCUAAUUUUUUGUGUUUUUAGUAGAGAUGGGGUUUCACCGCGUUAGUCAGGAUGGUCUUGAUCUCCUGACCUUGUGAUCCACCCGCCUCGGCCUCCCAAAGUGCUGGGAUUACAGGCGUGAGCCACCGUGCCCGGCCUGGUUGUGUUAUUCCAUCGAAAAACUGUUGCUGAAUUUUGAGGGCAAGCUUUUUCUGUUUUUAAUAAGUAAUAACAGGUAAAGCACACACAAAACAGUUCGCAUCUAUUCAUUCUUCUUAAAAUUAUAUUUUUUAUAUUUGUGCAAUUUUCUUUAGAAAAAUAGAUUUUAAGAUGGGUAACUGUAAACUGCAUUUUUAAUUUCAUUUUCUUACAAAUAAAAAAAUGAUCUGAGGGUUUUUAAAAAUUGUUUCUUUGAUUAAGGGAAUUUUUAUGGUAGGAAGCUCUGACUUGACAGUUCAGAACAUAGCUGUCUGUUUAUUAUAAAGAAGUGAUUGUAGAAAUACGUAAAGAAUUUUGGUAAGAAAAAAGUGGUUUAUAUAAUCUUGAGCCUCUGGGGGUUGUUAUUGUUAGAUAUUACAUAGGUUUAAUCUUUAAUGACAUAUAUAAUGAUAAAAUACAAAACUAGAUAACUUAUGAUUCUAAUUUGUGGUGUAUAUGCAAGGUAGAAAAAUUAGUAAGGAACACUAGAAUUUGUUAUAGUUAUCUCUAGGUGGAUUAUAGCUUUUCUUUUUCUUUAUAAUUUUAUAUAUUUUCUACAUUAUGUACUCUGAGCAUGUACUGCUCUCAUAACAUGAAAAAAAUUAUAAGCACUAAAAUGUUAUAGAGAAUGUUACUCAACUUGAAGUAAUUACCCAAAUAAUUUCACAAUUGAGGGAAAAAAUAACAUAGAAAUGAACCCAAACCAGCUUUUUUUCUCCGUGUAUUUUUUUCCAAGUCAAACCUAAGGCCUUGUUACUCCAAGUGUGAUCAGUAACCCAGCAGCAUAGGCAUCACGUGGAAGCUUGUUAGAAAUGCACAAUAUCAGACCCACCCCUGACCUACUGCAUCAGCAUCUGCAUUUUAACAAGAUCCUCAGGUGAUUCCUCCGCGUGUUAAAGUUUCAGAAGCACUGAUCUAAGACACUCUCCCUUAAUAACUAAAGCCUACUUCUAUUUUAUUCAUUCAUUGAUUAGGGCCGUCCUUUUGGUAAAACUUUAAAACAACAACUAUGCAGGCUACAGAAGGACUACCCAAGUUUUAAGGUAGAAUUCAUAUCACAACCUGGCCUUUUGAAAUAUGUUUUUAUUAAGCUAAAAAUGCAGUGGUCUGACAAGGGCUAAGAGAGGGGAAAAAAGCCAAAAAGCAUGAGUUCUUCCACUUUGUUUCUUCGUAACUAGAAGGAACAAGGGAGAAGUAAAUUAGGAUUUUCAAAAUAGCUUUCAGCUUUUUAAGAUUAGUGGCUUAUAAAAGAAAGAACUAAGGCCGGGCACAGUGGCUCACGCCUGUAAUCCCAGCACUUUGGGAGCACUUUGGCAGGUGGAUCACCUGAGGCCAGGAGUUUGAGACCAGCCUGAUCAACAUGGUGAAACCUCCGUCUCUAUUAAAAGUAAAAAAAUUAGCCAGGCAUGGUGGCACGUGCCUGUAAUCCCAGCUACUUGGGAGGCUGAGGCAGGAGAAUCGCUUGAACCCUGGAGGUGGAGGUUGCAGUGAGCCGAGAUCGCACCAUAGCACUCCAGCCUGGGCCACAGAGUGAGACUCCAUCUCAAUAAAAAAAGAACUGGAGUGUAGUUCUACACCCACUUCGUGUAAGGGCCACUCUCUAUGUGCCCAGAGUAAAGUUUCACCCUAUCACUACAUUCUGGACCUCAUUACAACAUUGAUUUAGUAGUAUUUUAUAAAGAUUUCAAGGCAUUCAACUAGAUUCUUUUAAUGGAAACAAGAUUCUAUUUCUUAAAUUUUGCUACUGAAAAGUUUAUUUUGAAAUUUUCUUUUUCCUACUGUCACUGACUUUUCUGUGAUGUUUUUAUACUCACUACAAGAACGAGAAAGUUGGUAUUGUCUGAUGGCAGCAUGCAGCCUGCUAACACUGGUUUAUUUUUCUCUAUGGAUACUGCCUGUUUUGUUUUUGUUUUAACUUGAGAUAACUUUACAAUGUGACAGAAGAGAAACUACAUUUUCCAAGAAAUGGUCACUUUAGUUGCUUUCCCCAUAAGUAGAAGUGUCUUGGCUCUGUACAUUUUCUGCCAUCUUCUUCAAGAUAGCUAAGUUAGUAUAUGAAAGUUGCCAUAUUUUGGAGCAGCCAGCUUCCAGAUUCUAAUUAUGUGUCUUUAAGCCCAUUUCUGUAAAUAUGCACUCAACGUUUGCACUUUUAUGUACAAAGAGACUUAGAGGCUUUCUAUGAUAACAGAUGUGUUACUCGUUCUAUAAAAUCAUUUCGCAUUAUGUCUUUUUAGUGGGCAAGUUCCUUUCCCCUUUUAUAGUGACAGGUACAGCAACACAAGGGCUCUGCCAUGUCUAGGUGAUAAUGUGGUUGAUGGUCUGCAUUUGCAAAGCAUAUUGUCAUUUUUUAGUAGGAAAAAUACUAAAGAUUGAUAAGUUUUUUUAUGUACUUCUUAAAAAUAUGCUUCUAUCACCAAUGAUGAAAAAAAUGAAACAAUUCGCAAGCAGUUAAGCCAUAAUGUGAGCUAAUCACUUUAUUUUGAAGAAAAGUAUUUUUAAACAGUUGAGCUAGUGAAUUUACUUUUAAAAUGUAUUGUGCUUACACAGUAGAUGGUUUUAUUUCCAUGAUGUUUUUUACUACAUAAUUAUACAUCUUAAUUACGUAAUUACUAUCAUAAUUAUUAUGUAAUUGCAUGUACUUCCACUAAUUACAAAAUCAGGAAGUGUAAUUAUCUAGUAAAAACUUUAUGAAAUUUCAUGCACUAAAAGUUAGUUAAAAGGCUAUUCCAGUGGUCUAGUGGAAGGCUUUCCAUGGUUAGUCUUCUUAGUCAUAACUUUAGUUUAGAGCUGGAACUCAUAGGCCAGGACAAGGAUAAGUGCCAACAGACCAACACUAAACUGAGUAUUGUGGUAUGGGUAAGAUAGACUUUGUCCCUUGUGAUUUAAAAAGUCAGAGAGCAUUUUAAUUUUUUUGUGACUAUGGAGUGUGGUAAGAAUAAUAUCUAAAUGUUUGAGGUAGGUACCACAAAAACUGUCAAUGGAAAGGGCAGUUCUUUCUUAGGAAGGAAUUGAUUAAUAGAAUCAACAAGGCAUUUAGGUUACACAACAGCAAGGUCUUCUAUAAUUCUGUAAUGUGAAUGGCUUAUUUAAUAGCUAUCUCUGCCUUUAAAAGCAAUAAUGAUAUUCAGUUUUCUGUUUCUUCAGUUUGGAGAAGGUGUUUUUCCAGUUUGUGUUUAUAUUUACUAAGAUAUGAGCAAACGUAUCAAGAGAGCAUACUCCUUUCUACUACUUGAUGUCAAAAGCAGCUUUUGAGACAUAAACAUAAGCGCACAAACAUGUAACAUCAGACCCUAAAUAAAGACAAAAGGUUUAAUUCAAUAAAGCUAUGAUGCCUUUACCAUUCAAAACGACAUAAAAAUUGCACAGUGAAACAAUAGUCAUGACAGCAAAUUAGAUAUGACAUCUAAAUUACACUACAAAGAGAAAUCCCAGAACCGUUUUUGGUCUGUAGGAGCCUAUUUUAGCCCAGGUUUAGAACCCAAUCUAGAGGCUCUGCUUUAUUGUCUAAGUAGGGUAAUGUUGUAGAAGACUAAUUGGACGUUGGUUGAAUUAAUUGCACAUCAAUUAGGAGGAAAGGGCUUGUAAUACUCAUGGCAGAGAAGUGAGUAGAUCCUUUAAGUAUCAUGAUGGAAUGUACUAUGAGUUUCAGGAAUUAAUAUUAUCAGUAUUUGGGUAAUAUCUGUAUAAUCUAUUACAACAUGACCUAAAUCAAGCACUUGGGGUUAGAUACAGGUAUACUAAUUUCCUCCCCAAAAUUAGUGCUUCUCACUAGAAAUGUAUUGAAACAGCCACUUAAAAUGUAUGAGUUAUUUCUUUUAAAAAUGUAGCCUUAAACAUUAAAAGGUUCAGCUCAGGAGAUCAGAUAUUCGUUUUUUUCUUAAAACUUUCUAACGAAACACUCAUUGUGGUAUUACCAGUUAUUGAAUUUGUGACUUUUUUAUACUAGCUGAAAUUUCCAAUAAGUGUGAAUUUUUUUAAAAAGUCAGUGAACGGUGUGAAAAUGCCAGUCCCAUUUGCUUCAGGCAAAUUAUAGGAUUUAUAUUUAUCCAGAAUUGUUUCAUGGUCUCAGAGAUGUUUGGGAUUUAAACAGAUUUAGUCUGACUCUGCUAUUUUUCUCUAGUAGUUAGGGGUUAUUUUAAAAUUGCAUAUUUUUUUCCUCUUGGGAAUCUUUUCUCAUUUACUUAGCCCAGAAUUUAAUGUCUUAAUCAUUUCUUAUUUGCCUUAACUCUAUUGUGAUAACAUUUCUUCUCAUGGUUUCAGAAGUGUUUAUGCUCCCUCUAUGAGACAGCACUGCCUCUCACGUUUCCUCUUAAUCUUUUGUUUUUGUUUUGGUGGUUGGUAUUUUUUAUUUUUAUUUUUUUUUACUAGUGCUUGUACCAUGCCAGAAUAGCCCUUAAUGGUUAAAAGCAAAGUGUUCACUUAAUCCUCAUCUUUUCAAUUAUAAUACAAAUUUCAUUUUGAAGCUGACAUUUAAACUGACAUUGUUGUGUUUUGUUUUGCUUUGCUUUCUUGCUUUGCAUGUGAAUUGGCAUAUGUCAUUAUCCUAUAAUUCUUGAUAAAUUUUUCAUAAUUAUCUAAGGGAAUCAACCGUAACUUUUGAAGUCUAAUUAUGUCCUUGUGAUGUCUCCAGUAACCCUGUAGGCCCAGGCCAAGAACUGAUGUUGAUUUUCACAUUAUUAAUCAGUGCCAUUUAUUAUUUUAUGCUGUACUAUCUGGUUCAUAUAAUGCUACCCUUCAUAUACAAAGAAAACCCAUCAUCAAUUUGACUCAUUCUUAAACUAGUUCUUCCUGUAGUUGUCAUGAAUUUAUUUAGAUCCAUCUGCAUUCUCUUACCUUGUGGCUAACAGGACAGUAACUAGACAGACUUAGUAGCCCAUCAUUGAGUUAAAUCAACACUGAUUACAUUCUCCCUGUAUAAAGGCCCUGGGAAACCCUUCUCUCCUUGGCCUGUGAGCCCUGCAAGCCCUAGCACCAUCCCCUAGAGCUUAAGGCUUAAACUAGUUCGUAGAAAGAUAGAUUUGCUGGCUAAUUUUAGACACUGAUGUGCUUUUCUUGUUCUAAGAAAUUAUUGUAAUUUCAAAUAGGGUCAAAAAAGCAGGUCUGUGUGUAAGUCUGUUACUCUCUGUCCCCUCUUCGUGCCCUGAACCCUUGCCCAGUUUAUUCAGCAAAUAUGUAUUGGGUCUCUGUCCUAUAUGAUAUUGCUUCUAGAAGUACCAAUACUUCUGACCAAUUGCUUAUUCAUGCAUUCACCUCUAAAUACCUCCUUUUUAUAGGACUCUACUUUUGUGGAGAACAUUCACAGCCAUUAUCUUUUACAUUUUCCAGACAAUUCCAUUGUAUACGGAUAUGUAGUUGACACUUCUGAGAUGAGAAACAACCCCAAAAGGAUGAAAUGACUCUCCCAAAGUAGCAAAGCUUAGAAGUGUUAAGAGCCCGGCUUUUCUUUCUGCCAUAUCUCAGCUGCCCUGUUCUUAAUCUAUUAGGGAAACUUCAGCCUGAAGACAAGUAACUCAAAUACAAGGGAAUGGUAUGAAUUGCUGAGGGAUCUCAGCAUAUACCUCAGGGAAGGUUUCCUGGUGGAGAUUUCCUGAGUUGGGCCUUAAAGAGUAUGUGAGAUUUUAAUAGGCACAGAUGCAGACAUGUAGUUUGAGACGAAGUUUUGCCUUUCUCACUUUUCUUUAAGUGCCCUAUUUAUCUUGCUUUUAUAAAGGGAGAACUUCCUUUGACAAAUGCAUCAUGAUUUGAAAGCAUAUCUGAAUUGAAAAUUUCGUCUAAAAGUGCUUAUUAAGAAGCAAAGCUUUAAACUCAGGACUAUAAGCUUGAAGGGCAUUAUUUUUUGAGAUAGGGUCUCGCUCUGUCACCUAGGCUGGAGUUCAGUGGCACGAUCUCUGCUCACUGCAGCCUCGACCUCCUGGGCUCAAGUGAUCCUCCCAUCCCAGUCCCCCGCCCCUAGUAGCUGAGACUGCAGGUGCGUGCCACCACGCCCAGCUAAUUUUUGUAUUUUUUUGUAGAGAUGGGGUUUCACCAUGUUGCCCAGGCUGGCCUCAAACUCCUGGACUCCAGCAAUCCACCCGCCUUAGCCUCCCAAAGUGCUGGGAUUACAGGCGUGAGCCACUGGGCCCGCUGUCCUUGAAGAGUAUUCUCUCUUCACUCUCCACUCUCCACUCUCCACUGUAACCAGUGGUGGUGCUUUGAAAGAAAUUGAUCCAUCCUACAGGAUACAUCUGUCAAAAGUGUAUCAAAAUGUUUUUCUAUCUUAAAUAAUUUAACUCAGAAUAUAAUAAUGUAAGUAUUUUGACAUGAAAAUUUACAUACUGUGAUAUAUCCACUUAUCUUAAAACAGACGUCUUUAACUAUAAAGAAAAGGAGUGUGGUAAGACAAAACAAAAUAGAAAUUGGAAUUAAAUGGGAUGACUGACAGACCAAACUAGUUUUAUUUAGACAAUAAAAAUUAAAGUCCUGUUAGCAUUAUGACGAAAAAAAUGUAAAAAUGUUUUACUUAAAGCAUGGCUGAUUUUUUGUUGUGUUUUGUUUUUUCACUAACACCAUGGUGAAAGUUUAAACAUGUAAGACCUGUUUAUGAAGUAAAUGUUUACUGCUGAACUAAUUCUUCAAGUUUACUGGUAUAUUAUAUAUUGCCUUACCAAAAAAAGUCGAUGCUGAAAAGUCAGUAAAAUCCACAGUAAAAGAAAGCGUCUGAACAGUAGUCUGUCUUGGGAAAUUAUUCAACAGAGUGCACUCUGGUCUCUGUUAGUGAAGGCUUUAUCACUUUUAACAAAUAAGCCGCAGUAAAUUUAUCAGUAUGCUACAAAGAAAUUUUCAAAAUAAUUAAGACUAAACUACACUUGUCAAAAUAAAUGAAUGAAAUACAAUUUUGAAUCAUCUUUCUUCACUUAUUGCUCAUUUGCAUAAUUCAGUAACUUACACAGGAGUCUUUCAGUCAUUGGUGUGAAUUAGCAAGGUUCUGCUAUUCCUUGUUGUACGGCAGGAAUUACCCUACCAUGUAAUUAGCUAUUCCAGACAUGGACUAACGGGAAAUACCAAAGGGCACAGCAAAAUCUAAAGAGGCAAGGCAGGGAAUCUAAAGACAAGAGACAAUCAAAGACACCCAACAAACUCAAGCUGGUAGACCACAGGGAAUUUUGAAUGAAGCCUCUUAAUUUAUUUUGAGAAUAAGAAAUCAGUAGUAUGAGAGAAAUCUCAACAAGAUUAGCUGACUAAGCCUACUUAAAAAAAAUAUCUCUAUAGUGCAUGGUGCGCCAGGUUAACCACUCCUGUUUGUUAGUCUGUAUACAGCUCAACAAAUAAGCGGCAAAGCUUUUCAUGGGUAUAUAGUGGCUUUCCAUUGAGGUUUUCACUCUUUGAAGGAGGUCAUUUAUACCAAUGAGAUCUGUAGAUGCAAAUUGCUUUCCCUAUAUGUGAGGGGUCAUUCCUUUCACAGCCAGCUUGCUCAUCUCUUUUAUAAAGGUUUUGUUAUUUUUGUACUGCUCCCAAAGGAAUGAUGAGAAUUAUGCCCCCCCACCCCCUGUCUAACUUAGCAUCCAAAUCUUUUCCCUCCAGCUCUGUGAAACUUUUGUGUGUUGAUCUUUGGAAACAAAACAAGCUGUUGGCAGCAGCCUUUAACUCUGAAUCAGGAAACUUUUUUCCUUCUUUCAACCUGAAAUAUCAUCUCUUUAGAUUUGCCUUUCUCGCCUAAUUCUAAGGAAAUAUCUUUUUCAUUGCAGCAGAGUGUCACUGUAACAUGCUACAGGCAUGUGGGAAUUCCUGGAAGCAGUGUCCUCAAAAUGCCAUUUUUAGUUUGGCUCAAAUGAUGUAAGCUCUCACGAACUAGAGGAAUAGAAAUGAAGGGAUCGAUUUAAGGGUUAGCUAUGAAAACCUAGCUUCUGAUCUCAUUACUGAAGUAAAGGGAAAGAUAAUAUUUGUCUUUGCCUAGGCUCUAAGGAAUCAUACAAACAUUCAACGGUUCUAGUUUGUUGUGUUCAGGAGUUUUAGGAAGGAGGAGCUUCAGGCAUACCAUGUGAAUGCUCUGUAAAAUGUUUGUUGUUUUGUUCCUUCCUUCUGCUAGCAUUUGUUGAACACCAAGGGCAUUGGCCUGGGUUUCUCAAAAGCAAUAUAGGGUAGUGAUUAAAAACUCAGUCUCUGGAGUGAGAGUGCCAGGUGCAAAUUUUGACUUUCCACCCCUUACUAGAUAAGUAACCUUGAAGUACAUCUAUAAAACAGGAAAAAAAUAGCACCUACCUCAAAGGGUUCUAAAUUCAGCAGGAUGACAUGGAAAUAGGCUAAUAUGUAAAACGUCUGGGACAUUAAACAGGCAAUACGUAAAAUGCUUAGGACAGUGCCUGGCACAUAGUAAGCAUGCAGUAAAUGUCAGUUGGUUUUAUUACUUCUGAGAAUACUUUGUCUAAACGACUAUCUAUUAUAGUACUUAGUGUUACAACUGUAUUUGAGUUGGUUUCUGCAGCCUGUCAUUGACCAUGUUUUGUUCAGAUUUGUAUCCUCAGCAUCUAGCACAACACCAAACAUGUAGCAAAUGCUCGAUUCAUUUUUACCAAAUGGUUACAGUAUGAAAAAAGCAUGGUCCCUGUUCUCAAGGAGCUUAAAAUAUAUCUUGAUAACUGUGUUUUAGUUUUCUUAUCUAUUGAAAUAGCAUCAUGUCAGAAGUGUAUUAAAAAGAAAACUUUAGUUCUCAGUCUUCCAUACUUAAUGGAAGAAGUUGAAACACGAAUAAUCUGCAAGCCAGAUUUCUGAUUGAGUAGGUCUGGGGUGGGACCCAGGCGGCAGUGUAUUUAAAAAUCUCCGCAGGUGAUUCUGAUGCACACCCACAGUGUUGGGAAUCUCUGAGUUAGUGAAACUCUUCAAACUUUAAUAUUGCUUCUUGUCAAAUAUGCAUUAAGUUUGACUUUGAUAUAGAAAGGGAGACUGGGUGGCAUCUAGAUAACAAUUUAAACAGACAGUAGAAAGGAAAAUGAAGUCAAACACAAGAAUUAUUUCCUAGAUAAAGGAAGCAUUUAUGGUGCUGUAUACGCUAAUGUAGCAUCAAAGAUAAAGUGAAGAAAAAUAGGCUAGGGAAAAGUAAGCAAGAAGGAACUGUUUUCUGGUAAUGAGCAAACUGAAGAUGAAAUAAAUGCAUUUCAACAAAAUUGGCUAUAAAGCACAUUAUUUUCCCCCAUUAACUUGCGUCAUGAAUGAAGGAAUAGGGCUGCUGGGGAGGAUGGGGGAUCUUUCAAGGAGACUGGAUAGGUAACUGGGGAGAUAUUAAGGUGGAGGCUAACCCAAACGUGGUACUUAGGAGCUUCUGUGGUUUGGAUUUCUGAGACCAUUCCCACCUCCUGUCCUCUUCUACUUACCUUGACACUCAGCUGACUGGAUCCUGGGUAGAGCAGCCUUCCGCAACUUUAUAAUUUUGCACGUCCUCCAAGCGGUCUGGAACAGGAUGGUAGUAGUAGAGGGUUUAGGAGGAUAUUCCUGUGUCCUGUGCUCAUCUCUUGGGGUGCUCAUCUCUUGGGGUGCUCAUCUUACCUGGGGUGUCCAGGCAGGAGAAAUAGCUUGACUGGCUAUAGCUGGAGUUAUAAAAUAGUCUCAGAUCACCCCUUUUUGCCUAGAAGGAUUAGGACUGCACCUUGUUGGUACCCACAAAUUAGACCCUUCUUCACCAGUCCCUGAGCAGGCCUUGACUCCACUAUGGCCACAUCCUUUGGCUGGUGUGGUUUCCCUGCCUGGGUUAGCCAACCUCAACCCAGUCUCUGUUCAUAUUCUAUUCAUACUUUAAGGCCUCCCAGCCAUAAGUGAUCUCUUUGUCCUCUAAACUCCUGUAGUUCUUAAGCACUGUCCCUCUUACAUUAUAAUUAUUUGAGGACAGGGAUCAUGCUUGAUACAUUAUUUUAUGUCUGAUGGCAACUUGCUCAUGAUAGGAGCCUAAUAAAUGGUAUGUUAAAUUAAUGUUUUCUGUAAUAGAGCACUUUCUGACUCCAUCCUCUUUUCUCUGCUAUUUAUUUCCUAUUAUGUCCUUCAACUGUGUCAUAAAAAAUUUUCUAUCCAUGUAUGUAUACAUUCAUCAAACAUUUAGCCCAUACCAUCUCCUCAUUCCACAUGGACUUAAUUUCCCACCUUAAUCUGUCUACUUUCUGACAAUUACUAAUAGAGUUGGGCUGUGAUAUCAUGUAUCUCCAGAAGAUUACAUAAAUUCCAGCCUAGAAAUUUCUUUGUUUAAACCUUUAGGUUAUAUAAAUCAAACUGAUGCUCAGUCAUAUUAGUGGGAUUAAGUUUGAAAGUCUAAAAUCAUACUUCAAAUGAGGACUGUCUCAACCCAGGCACACUCCUUGCCCUCCAGAAUUUAUAUACAUUUGAUAGCAGCUGGUUGUUUUCCCUGCAGAUUCUUUUUUUUUUUUUUUUUUUUUUUUUUUUUUUUUUUUUUUGAGACAGAGUCUCACUCUGUUGCCCAGGCUAGAGUGCAUUGGCGCAAUCACGGCUCACUGCAGCCUUGACUCCCCAGGUUCAGGUGACCCUCCCACUUAAGCCUCCCAAGUAGCUGUGACUACAGGCAUGUGCCACCAUGCCUGGCUAAUUUUUUGUAUUUUUUUUUUAGAGACAAGGUUUUGCCAUGUUGCUCAAGUUGGUCUGCAACUCCUGAACUGAAGAGAUCCGCCUGCCUUGGCCUCCCAAAGUGUUGGGAUUACAGGCAGGAGCCACCGCAUCCAGCCACCUGCAGAUUUUUCUAGUGAUUCACAGUUUUAGCUCUCUGCUCCAGAUGUGUUAUUUGGUUGGCUAGCCUUUAAUAUAUCUUGAAAUGUCUGGAGGCCAACUCCAGAAAGCUCUCGUGAAGGUGGGAAGGUGAAGAACCGCUAAGAGACUUUCAGACUGGUUUUCUCUUAUCACCCAUGUGACUUUCAGUUGAGCAGCAUGCAGGCACACGUAUUAAUGGCAAUGUAGGUUUGUAAACAAUACUACUAAUAGGCUGGGGCUGGGGGAGAAAAAUAGCCCACAAGAAAUCUGGAGAUACCUGUCUUGAGUGUAACCUGCAAGAUAUACUCUAACAGAGUAAUCAUUGCACGAUAUCAUUGUGGGAGACUGAGCGAGUUAGAAAAUCUAUUCCUGGUUUGUCGCUGACUCACUUUGUGGCAUGGGCAAACCAUUAUUACUCUUUGAUUUAGUUGUUUUAUUUGUUCGAAAAAGGGAAAAUAACAUGUGUUUAAAAAGCACUCUGAAAUUCCUCUGAAAGGAGGUCUAUAAGUGCAAAGUACUAUUGUUGUUUUUAUUAUUAUUAUUAGUGUUCUAGUAUGGUUUAGUUUUAUGCCAUGUAGGUCACAGAUGUUUCAAUUCUUCCGACUGAUGAAUUACAAAACACUUCCAUCUCAUUCUGUUUUAUAGCGUUGAUAACAGUUUAGCACAUCUUUGUUUUAACCCCAGUUAAAGUAUAUGUCCAAAAUAGACCUCAUUAAUAAAAUACAAUUACUAAAUUAAA